ACAGUGGAUCCGGAAGCACAGGAGACCAAGAGACCAGAGAUACCAGGAUGAGAGAUAGGACCCCUGGUUGCCAGGUUCGAGAAGUCCUAGGCUGAGUCCCUGGAAAUGCCAGCCGCCAGUGGUCGCACUUGGAGGGUCUCGCCGCCAGUGGAAGGAGCCACCGCCCCCGCCCGACCAUGGCCGAGGAGCUGGUCUUAGAGAGGUGUGAUCUGGAGCUGGAGACCAAUGGCCGAGACCACCACACGGCCGACCUGUGCCGGGAGAAGCUGGUGGUGCGACGGGGCCAGCCCUUCUGGCUGACCCUGCACUUUGAGGGCCGCAACUACGAGGCCAGUGUAGACAGUCUCACCUUCAGUGUCGUGACCGGCCCAGCCCCUAGCCAGGAGGCCGGGACCAAGGCCCGUUUUCCACUAAGAGAUGCUGUGGAGGAGGGUGACUGGACAGCCACCGUGGUGGACCAGCAAGACUGCACCCUCUCGCUGCAGCUCACCACCCCGGCCAACGCCCCCAUCGGCCUGUAUCGCCUCAGCCUGGAGGCCUCCACUGGCUACCAGGGAUCCAGCUUUGUGCUGGGCCACUUCAUUUUGCUCUUCAACGCCUGGUGCCCAGCGGAUGCUGUGUACCUGGACUCGGAAGAGGAGCGGCAGGAGUAUGUCCUCACCCAGCAGGGCUUUAUCUACCAGGGCUCGGCCAAGUUCAUCAAGAACAUACCUUGGAAUUUUGGGCAGUUUGAAGAUGGGAUCCUAGACAUCUGCCUGAUCCUUCUAGAUGUCAACCCCAAGUUCCUGAAGAACGCCGGCCGUGACUGCUCCCGCCGCAGCAGCCCCGUCUACGUGGGCCGGGUGGUGAGUGGCAUGGUCAACUGCAACGAUGACCAGGGUGUGCUGCUGGGACGCUGGGACAACAACUACGGGGACGGCGUCAGCCCCAUGUCCUGGAUCGGCAGCGUGGACAUCCUGCGGCGCUGGAAGAACCACGGCUGCCAGCGCGUCAAGUAUGGCCAGUGCUGGGUCUUCGCCGCCGUGGCCUGCACAGUGCUGAGGUGCCUGGGCAUCCCUACCCGCGUCGUGACCAACUACAACUCGGCCCAUGACCAGAACAGCAACCUUCUCAUCGAGUACUUCCGCAAUGAGUUUGGGGAGAUCCAGGGUGACAAGAGCGAGAUGAUCUGGAACUUCCACUGCUGGGUGGAGUCGUGGAUGACCAGGCCGGACCUGCAGCCGGGGUACGAGGGCUGGCAGGCCCUGGACCCAACGCCCCAGGAGAAGAGCGAAGGGACGUACUGCUGUGGCCCAGUUCCAGUUCGUGCCAUCAAGGAGGGCGACCUGAGCACCAAGUACGAUGCGCCCUUUGUCUUUGCGGAGGUCAAUGCCGACGUGGUAGACUGGAUCCAGCAGGACGAUGGGUCUGUGCACAAAUCCAUCAACCGUUCCCUGAUCGUUGGGCUGAAGAUCAGCACUAAGAGCGUGGGCCGAGACGAGCGGGAGGAUAUCACCCACACCUACAAAUACCCAGAGGGGUCCUCAGAGGAGAGGGAGGCCUUCACAAGGGCGAACCACCUGAACAAACUGGCCGAGAAGGAGGAGACAGGGAUGGCCAUGCGGAUCCGUGUGGGCCAGAGCAUGAACAUGGGCAGUGACUUUGACGUCUUUGCCCACAUCACCAACAACACCGCUGAGGAGUACGUCUGCCGCCUCCUGCUCUGUGCCCGCACCGUCAGCUACAAUGGGAUCUUGGGGCCCGAGUGUGGCACCAAGUACCUGCUCAACCUCAACCUGGAGCCUUUCUCUGAGAAGAGCGUUCCUCUUUGCAUCCUCUAUGAGAAAUACCGUGACUGCCUUACGGAGUCCAACCUCAUCAAGGUGCGGGCCCUCCUCGUGGAGCCAGUUAUCAACAGCUACCUGCUGGCUGAGAGGGACCUCUACCUGGAGAAUCCAGAAAUCAAGAUCCGGAUCCUUGGGGAGCCCAAGCAGAAACGCAAGCUGGUGGCUGAGGUGUCCCUGCAGAACCCGCUCCCUGUGGCCCUGGAAGGCUGCACCUUCACUGUGGAGGGGGCCGGCCUGACUGAGGAGCAGAAGACGGUGGAGAUCCCAGACCCCGUGGAGGCAGGGGAGGAAGUUAAGGUGAGAAUGGACCUGCUGCCGCUCCACAUGGGCCUCCACAAGCUGGUGGUGAACUUCGAGAGCGACAAGCUGAAGGCUGUGAAGGGCUUCCGGAAUGUCAUCAUUGGCCCCGCCUAAGGGACCCCUGCUCCCAGCCUGCUGAGAGCCCCCACCUUGAUCCCAAUCCUUAUCCCAAGCUAGUGAGCAAAAUAUGCCCCUUCUUGGGCCCCAGACCCCAGGGCAGGGUGGGCAGCCUAUGGGGGCUCUCGGAAAUGGAAUGUGCCCCUGGCCCAUCUCAGCCUCCUGAGCCUGUGGGUCCCCACUCACCCCCUUUGCUGUGAGGAAUGCUCUGUGCCAGAAACAGUGGGAGCCCUGACCUUGGCUGACUGGGGCUGGGGUGAGAGAGGAAAGACCUACAUUCCCUCUCCUGCCCAGAUGCCCUUUGGAAAGCCAUUGACCACCCACCAUAUUGUUUGAUCUACUUCAUAGCUCCUUGGAGCAGGCAAAAAAGGGACAGCAUGCCCCUUGGCUGGAUCAGGGAAUCCAGCUCCCUAGACUGCAUCCCGUACCUCUUCCCAUGACUGCACCCAGCUCCAGGGGCCCUUGGGACAGCCAGAGCUGGGUGGGGACAGUGAUAGGCCCAAGGUCCCCUCCACAUCCCAGCAGCCCAAGCUUAAUAGCCCUCCCCCUCAACCUCACCAUUGUGAAGCACCUACUAUGUGCUGGGUGCCUCCCACACUUGCUGGGGCUCACGGGGCCUCCAACCCAUUUAAUCACCAUGGGAAACUGUUGUGGGCGCUGCUUCCAGGAUAAGGAGACUGAGGCUUAGAGAGAGGAGGCAGCCCCCUCCACACCAGUGGCCUCGUGGUUAUUAGCAAGGCUGGGUAAUGUGAAGGCCCAAGAGCAGAGUCUGGGCCUCUGACUCUGAGUCCACUGCUCCAUUUAUAACCCCAGCCUGACCUGAGACUGUCGGAGAGGCUGUCUGGGGCCUUUAUCAAAAAAAGACUCAGCCAAGACAAGGAGGUAGAGAGGGGACUGGGGGACUGGGAGUCAGAGCCCUGGCUGGGUUCAGGUCCCACGUCUGGCCAGGCACUGCCUUCUCCUCUCUGGGCCUUUGUUUCCUUGUUGGUCAGAGGAGUGAUUGAACCAGCUCAUCUCCAAGGAUCCUCUCCACUCCAUGUUUGCAAUGCUUUUAUAUGGCCCAGCCUUGUAAAUAACCACAAGGUCCACUCCCUGCUCCACGAAGCCUUAAGCCAUAGGCCCAGGAUAUUUCUGAGAGUGAAACCAUGACUGUGACCACCUUCUGUCCCCAGCCCUGUCCUGGUUCCUUCCUAUGCCCAGGUACCACCCUUCAGACCCCAGUUCUAGGGGAGAAGAGCCCUGGACACCCCUGCUCUACCCAUGAGCCUGCCCGCUGCAAUGCCUAGACUUCCCAACAGCCUUAGCUGCCAGUGCUGGUCACUAACCAACAAGGUUGGCACCCCAGCUACCCCUUCUUUGCAGGGCUAAGGCCCCCAAACAUAGCCCCUGCCCCGGAGGAAGCUUGGGGAACCCAUGAGUUGUCAGCUUUGACUUUAUCUCCUGCUCUUUCUACAUGACUGGGCCUCCCUUGGGCUGGAAGAAUUGGGGAUUCUCUAUUGGAGGUGAGAUCACAGCCUCCAGGGCCCCCCAAAUCCCAGGGAAGGACUUGGAGAGAAUCAUGCUGUUGCAUUUAGAACUUUCUGCUUUGCACAGGAAAGAGUCACACAAUUAAUCAACAUGUAUAUUUUCUCUAUACAUAGAGCUCUAUUUCUCUACGGUUUUAUAAAAGCCUUGGGUUCCAACCAGGCAGUAGAUGUGCUUCUGAACCGCAAGGAGCAAACACUGAAAUAAAAUAGUUUAUUUUUCACACUCAAACUAGGUCUGGUCUGUUCCUUUAUGAGUUUGGAGGGAGAUGGGUAGGUGAGCUCGCUCACACCUGGACCCCCACUUCCUGCCUAGGAGUCUUUCCUGAGCCUCAGCCCUGUCCCUGCGUUUAAACUUUACUGGCAUUCAAGGUCCUACACAGGCUGGCUCCAUCUCCGGCCCCUUCCACCAACAGUCUGUUUUUGGGCCACAAUUAACUUCCUGUAUCCCCAGAACACCCUGCGUAGUUGUCUACCUCUUGGCUUUUGUGUAUGUAGUUCCCUGAGCCUGGAGUGCCCCUCCUUUUCUUUCCCUGCUUGGCAAACUCCUACUCAUCCUAUAAUGCUUAACACCAAAGUCACCUCUUCUGUGAAACCUUCCUUGAUAUCUUUUCGGGUCCCCAGAGUCCUGGAAUAUGGACCAAUUCAAACAUUUAUCACAGUAAAUUUUACUUCCACGUUGGCCUAUCUGUCCCCUUCUCCAUCCUAUCUGAAGCCCUCGAGGCAGGGACCACGUAUCUCUUAAAUACACUAAUAAAUGCUGAAUUGGUAAAUGAAUGUUUCCUAACUCAACUCCCACAAGACCUGUGCUGUCCCAUAGAAAUAAUACAUGAGCCACAAAUGCAAGCCACAUAUGUAAUUUAGAAUUUUCUAGUGACCACAUUGAAAACAGUAAAAAAGCCAUAGGUGGAAUUAGCUUUAAUAAUGUAUUUUAUUUAAUCCAAUAUAUCCAAAACAUUAUUUCAACAUGUAAUCAAUAUAAGAAUUAGUAAGGUAUUUGACCUUCUUAUUUUUGUACUCAAUCUUUGAAAUGUGGUGUGUGUUUUAUACUGACAGCAGGUCUCAAUUUGAACUAGCUGCAUUUCAAGUGCUCGGUAGCCAGUCUGGCUAGUACUGGAUGAAGCAGGUCUAGACUGCGAUUCCGUGGAUGUGCAGACUUGGUCAUUCAUCUCAUUCCCCACCAUCGAAGCACUCAUGAGUAUCUGUUGAAUGAAUAGAUGAUGGGGACAGUCCCCACCCUUGGGAAGUCAUGUAGAAAGACAUGACAUGCACAUAAAAAAUAAAUCAAAAUAAAAACAUGACAUCACG